GCACUCGCGGGUGCGCGCGCGGACGGCCGGGCGGCGGCGGCUCCCGGAGGUGGUGGCUUCACUUUCCAGGACUCAGGGGCAGCCACAGCGACAGCCGCGGGCAGCAGCCUCAGGAGCCGGAGCUGGAACGGCCGGGGGCGGCGGCAGCGGCGGCGCUGAGGGAUCUAAAAUGUCCACUGAGGCACAAAGAGUUGAUGACAGUCCAAGCACUAGUGGAGGAAGUUCCGAUGGAGAUCAACGUGAAAGUGUUCAGCAAGAACCAGAAAGAGAACAAGUUCAGCCCAAGAAAAAGGAGGGAAAAAUAUCCAGCAAAACCGCUGCUAAAUUGUCAACUAGUGCUAAAAGAAUUCAGAAGGAACUUGCAGAAAUCACAUUGGACCCUCCUCCCAACUGUAGUGCUGGACCCAAAGGAGACAACAUUUAUGAAUGGAGGUCAACUAUAUUGGGACCCCCAGGAUCUGUCUAUGAAGGAGGGGUGUUCUUUCUUGACAUUACCUUUUCACCAGACUAUCCGUUUAAACCCCCUAAGGUUACCUUCCGAACAAGAAUCUAUCACUGUAAUAUUAACAGCCAAGGUGUGAUCUGUCUGGACAUCUUAAAGGACAACUGGAGUCCGGCUUUAACUAUUUCUAAAGUUCUCCUCUCCAUCUGCUCACUUCUUACAGAUUGCAACCCUGGUGAUUUCGAAGCCUGGCCUGCUUUGCCUCCAAGUCAGCUGAAAUGGAAUCUGUUACCCUGAAUAAGCCUGUAUAUGACAGCCUGUUCUCUCUACAGAUAUUCCUGCUUAAAGGAAUAGAUUCAUUCCACCAAAGCCUUCUCUCAGCAAUCAAAAAGACUUCUGUUCAGUGAACUAGUUUUUUUUUUUUGCUCCGUUUCAGAAAAUUACAAAUGCAUUCUGCAAAAACUUAAAAAUCACUCCUAACUAAAGCAGAACCACAUAAGUAAAAGAAAUAGAUUUUGAAAUAAUGCUAUUGAUAGUAAGAACAAGCCUAAAAAUAAUGUUCCAUAAAACCAAAGACAGCCUGCCUCAUAUGAGACUAGAAGAGAAUUUGUAAAAUACAUGCUAACAUUUAGUUUAUCACACUUUUUAACACAUAAAAAUAAAGUUUCCUAAUUGGUUUUUAUGAAUGUUGACACUUCUAGAAUCUUAAAUAGAGUUGUUUAUUUUAAAGUAGUCAAAUGUCCAUUCUUUUGCUUAAUGGACUUAUUUCACACUGUUAUCUGGUACACUUUCAAUCUCUGUAGGUUUUUUUACCUACAGAGGUAGGAAAGAUUAGGUUAGAUUGAAGUUUAUCUUAAAUCUAUCUUCAAAUUAUCACAAAAACAAGUUUGAUAGAAUAGGAAUAAAUAAGAUUUUCCUACACUGAAUCUGUAGAGCUAUUUUAACCCGGAAAUGCUGUCACCUCAAAAAUAGGCCUUGUAUAAUGAUACAAAUUUAACUCACUUAAAAAAUACUUUCUCACUCUUAUCCAUACAUAAACUUAUUUUCUAAAUCUUUUUCAUACUCUUUUUGUAAUUUGCACUUGUCUCUUUAAAGAAUUUUUGGUCCAUUCCAACACAGAUGUUCUUUAGGGUAUGACUACCCAUCCUUAUCAGCAUGAUAUUUGUAGACAGCAGAUGUAGAUUUGAAAACCAGUUUAAUUGUUUAUUAGUCAUAUCACAUUGGAUGGGUCACUUAACUUUCCACAGGCUUAGUUUUUGAUAUAAAAUUGGGAUUAGUACCAGCCCUGCCUAAAUCACUGGAUUCCUCUGAGGUUAAAAUGAGAUGGUAUAUGUGAAAGCCAUUUAUAAAUGGUAAUGUGUUGUUGAUAUUGUUACCCAGAGUAUUUGGGACACCAAAUGGGCCCACAAUAGGUGACCGAUAAACACCUACUCAGUUGAAUUUAACUGGGGAGAUAGUAUCGAAUAGUAUCUAACGCCGUCACCUCAACAUUGACACUUGGAUUUUACAAUCGAAAAAAGCUGAACCUUGACUUAGUAGGAUUAUCACUCAGGUGGCAGAUGUCCAAACGUUAUCAGCCAGUCGAUGGGUGCACCAGCAAUAAUCAUUCUGUUUUCAAUGCAAUUGUCUAGGUAGAUCUAACUGCUGGUCUUAUUAGGCCACCACUUCAUGAUGGUGUUUAUUGAGCCUGAUAGAGCAUUCUUUUUUUUUUUUUUUUUUUUUUUGAGAUGGAGUCUCGCUCUGUCGCCCAGGCUGGAUUGCAAUGGCACGAUCUCAGCUCACUGCAUCCUCUCCUCCCGGGUUCAAGCGAUUCUCCUGCCUCAGCCUCCCGAGUAGCUGGGUCUACAGGCCCCACCACCAUGCCUGGCUAAUUUUUUGUAUUUUUAGUAGAGACAAGGCUUCACCGUGUUAGCCAGGAUGGUCUCAAUCUCCUGACCUCGUGAUCCGCCCGCCUCGGCCUCCCAAAGUGCUGGGAUGACAGGCGUGAGCCACCCAACCAGCCAAGCAUUCUUAUUUGUUAGACGUUACCUGGCUUUUUCUGAGUUUAGUCUUGCUUACUAAACAUUAUUUAAUUUGUGAAUUGCCAAAGUUGAGAAUACCAUUGGGGAAUCAAAUUUCUGUGCUUUCUUAUUUGUAAGUACUUUCUUCUGGAGUCAUUAUUUAACACAUAAAAUUUAAGUUCUAUUUGGUUUCAUCUUUUGAAGUUUGUUUUUGCUAUUUUGUGGACUUUUUAAAAACUCUUAGAUGUUUGGUAAUAUUCUUUAUAUGAAAUCUGUUUCUUUAACAAUUAUUUAAAAUGUGCUUAUAUUAUGGCCUUCAGACCUAUUUAAAAAAUGGGUAUUUUACCUCAUGCAAAAUUAAUCAUUGUGAGAACACUGACAAUUAGAAGAUCAACAGUUUUCCUUUACCUGAUGCUUAGUUUACAGAGUUAUGGCUAUAAAUAUUUCUAACCUUUUUUUCCUUCUUGAGACGUGUAUAGGUCUGUAUAUCAUCUAGCAUUAUUUUAUUAAUCUCAUUUCUAUUUGUCUGCUCUACUACUGUUACUCUCUAAAGUGUUUUUGAGCUUGUUUUGUUCUAAACUCAGUUAUGAUGUAUCAUUUAAAAUUUUCCCCCAAAUAUGUAUGACUCUUAUGAGACAGUCAGAAAGUUGACAAUGAAACAUUUGAUAUUGAGAAAUUAUUGCCAGAAAUUUUUGAGCAUGACAAUGGAAUUGUACCUGUCCUUACCUUUUAGACAUCUGUACUGGACUAUUUGCAAAUAAAAUUCUUUGAUAUAUGGAA